GAGACGGAGCCGGAAGGCCGUUAUUCAGAGGCGGCUCCGAGCCUCCCCUUCGCCUUCUGGAUGCUCUGAGCUCCUCAACUUGGCGUUCAGGGCCCUGCAUUGUCUGGUCCGUUUUCACCGGAGAGUCCAGCAACUGACACUUUCUUCCCUUAAACCUGUUGGGCGGUUCAUUCCUUUGAGCUACUGUACAUGCUCUUCCUUCUGCCGAGCUCCCCGGAUUAUGGUGCACUGAGAAGGCAUCUGGAAGCCUGGGCCCUCAUGGCAUCCAACGAUAAAGGCAUGGCACCCUCGCUGGGCUCUCCCUGGGCCUCCCAGAUGGGGCCCUGGGAUGCCAUCCUCAAGGCUGUCAAAGACCAGCUCCCGUCUCUGGACUCAGACUCCCCUUUGUCGGACUAUGGGGAAGAGGAGCUGUUCAUCUUCCAGCGAAACCAAACCUCCCUGAUUCCAGACCUGUCGGAGGAGCUGGCUGAAGAUCCUGCCGAUGGCGACAAGUCCAGGGCCUGGGUCGCUGCAGCUGAAGAGUCCCUUCCCGAGCCAGUUCUGGUGCCUGCAGAAUUGGCCACAGAACCUGGGUGCAGACAGAACACAAGGACAAAGGAUGCAUCCUCUCAGGAAGGAAGAGACCCUGGCAGGCCUUUUGAAAGCUCUGGUGAGGUCAGCGCUCUUCUUGGGAUGGCCGAGGAGCCCCCCAGGUGGCUGGAAGGCGACCUUGGAAGCCUGUCUUUCAACACCAAAGGAUCCCAGGGUCCUCCCUGGGACCCACAGGCCGAAGCCACUCUCUCCUGCCAUGAAGGAGACCCAAAGGCAGAGCCCCUCAGCACUGCCUCACAAGAAUCUGUGAACCGCCGGGCCCUCCGACAGGAGAGAAGGAAGAUGAUAGAGACGGACAUCCUCCAGAAAGUCACCCGGGAUGCCUGCGGCCCGACCAGCAGUGACAAAGGUGGGGUGAAGGAGGCGCCCUGCCACGCUGCGGAGUCAGCUCCCAGAUCCAAAAUGCCCCUCGUGGAGCCUCCGGAGGGACCACCAGUGCUCUCGCUCCAGCAACUUGAAGCGUGGGAUUUGGAUGACAUCCUUCAGAGUCUGGCGGGACAAGAAGACAACCAGGGAAAUCGUGCACCUGGAACUGUGUGGUGGGCAGCUGACCACCGCCAAGUUCAAGACCGCAUGGUGCCGAGCGCCCACAACAGGCUCAUGGAACAGCUGGCCCUCCUGUGCACCACGCAGUCCAAGGCCUCUGCUUGUGCCCGGAAGGUGCCUGCCGACACUCCCCAGGACACCAAAGAGGCAGAUUCAGGAAGCAGAUGUGCCUCAAGGAAGCAGGGCUCCCAGGCUGGGCCAGGCCCGCAGCUGGCCCAGGGCAUGAGGCUUAACGCAGAGUCCCCCACCAUCUUUAUUGACCUGCGGCAGAUGGAGCUACCAGACCACCUGUCCCCAGAAAGCUCCAGCCACAGCUCCUCUGACAGUGAGGAGGAGGAGGAGGAAGAGAUGGCAGCUCUGGGAGACGCAGAGGGGGCAUCUCCUUCCUCCCUGGGGCUACGGACCUGUACCGGGAAAAGCCAGCUUCUCCAGCAGCUCAGGGCCUUUCAGAAGGGGACAGCCCAGCCCGAGCUGCCUGCCAGCAAGGGGCCCGCGGGUGGGAGGGCUCAGGCCCCUGAAGACACAGCUGGAUCACGAACUGGGAGGAAGCAACACAUGAAGCUCUGUGCCAAGGGGCAGAGCGCCCAGGCUCGACUCCCAAGAGGCAGGCCCAGAGCCCUGGGGGAUGUUCCUGAGCCAGGGGCAGCCAGGGAGGCCCUGAUGCCUCCUCUGGAGCAACUAUAGCUGCCUCAGGAUGUGUCCUGCUGUCUGCCCCGUGGGAAGAGCAGAGAAAUCAUCACCACCUUGGGCCCCACGGUGCCACGGGCUCAGGCAGCACAGUAGGGCGCCGGGCCUUUGGGACAGUGUCCCAGCUUCCCCUGGGGUUCACCCCUGGCUGCCAGGCCACUGAGGAUGGGCAGGGGUCUCUUCUCAUCAAGCCUUGUACCAGGCAAAAGACAGGCCCUGCUUGGCCGUGGUCACUGGCCGCCAAGAUCAGGGCUACAGAUGUCUGCUCUCUGGACCCCACGUGAUCUGGCCACUGGGGACCCCCACCCGACCCCACUCCCAAUGAUGAGGGGCAUUUUCAUUGCAAGUCAAAGGCAAGACAGGCUUCCAUAAAGUCCCAGGAGGUCCCUCCUGUAGGGCACAAGGCCAGGCUGCCUCCCAGCCCCCAGGCCCUCUCCCACCUACAGAGACCCUCCCCUGCCCCCUCCACUCCGGGGCCUGUGCCGCCAGAACCGGGCUCUGCCCCCAUACGCUGCCCUCGCAGCCUGGCGGCCUCCGCUGUGGCUGCCUAGCUGUCAAGAGCAAAGGCUUUUUUUUUCUUCAACCCCAUUUUCUUCCAUUUCUCCCACCUUUUUAAUGCCAGUAACCUCACUGAGAAUGUUUUACAGUGAUGGAAAAUAAACUCUGUUCCAAGUUCAA